GACAGCUUCCGCACAAAGCGCGGUCUAUUUCUCCGCUGAAAGGAGCGUGAGGGUGCGGCCGUUGGGAAAUAAAGGCUGCAGGGCGAGGAGUGGGGAAAGAGAAAAACCUGAAAGGUUAAAGACUGCCAAAGUGAGGGAGCAUCAGAAGGUUGGAGAGUAGUGGGUGAGGGGACUGGUUCUAGGGACUAAUGGGCGACACUGAGCAUGCCCAAGUGUUUCCAAGGACCGCAGAGAAAACGCCCCCUUUACUUGGCCUAUGCGGCGACUGCGGCUGUACCUGCUCAGUUCCCGGCUCUGGGGACACAGAAGAAUCACGCCUCUGCCCUGGUAGAACUCUCCAUCUAGUGGGGAGCCAGACUUGGGCACAAGGAAGCAUGCCUCAAUUGCUACGUGUGGCAAGCGUGGGGGUACAGUAGGAAGGCUGACAGCAACGGGGAGGACCUAGGAAGGCUUCAUGAAGAUAAUAGCAUUGGGAUAGGUUUUGAGGAUGGGUAGGAUACAUACAGGUGGAAGUGGAGACAAGGGUGCUCAAAAAACAUGGAACGGGUGCCGGGGCAAAGGCAUGAAGCAGGAGCCCUCUGCAAGUGCUGGGUAGUCUCACGUGGCGGCAGAUGGCCGCAGGCUGCUGACCUGGGCUCCCAGGUAGAACUAAGGGCUGUUUCCUGCUCCCACAGCUCCUCCACUUCCUCCAACACAGUGAAUGGAAAUUAUGCUUCUUCCUCUGUCUACUAAACUGUGCGGUCCUUCAAGCUAGGAAAAGAGCCUGUCACCUUUCCAUCCCCCGUGAGGACUCCAGGGCUUGGCCAAGAUGGACCGUUAAAACUGAUUGACCUGACAGUCCUGUCUGAUACUCAGCGGUGAGACUGUCAAGGUGGGCCAGGGUUCUGUGGCUGAUGUCUCAACAUCUGGCUCACAAGCAGCUCAGACCAGCUUGUCCAAGCCAGCCCUCCUGUCCCCGCACCAAACCUGCAGCCUCACCAGCAUUCGUCCUCUGGGUCGGGCACCGGUUUCCUCCCACUGCACCAGCAGAAACCAGAGACUCCUUCUUAUCCCUCCCCCUACCCAGUCCGAUUCAUCACCAAGUCUCGCCAUGUUGCCUUUUAUAUUUCUCUGAAAUCUGUGCACCUCUCCUCACCCUAUUGUCACCUUCCUAACCUGAGCCCCUUCAUUUUUGGCCUGGCUCCUUCCUUCCUUCCUUCCUUCUUUCCUUCCUUCCUUUCUUUCUUUCUCUCUCUCUCUUUCUUUUUUCUUUUUCUUUUUCUUUUGACGGAGUUUUGCUCUUGUUGCCCAGGCAAUAGUGCAAUGGCACAAUCUUGACUCACUGCAACCUCUGUCUCCCAAGUUCAAGCAAUUCUCAUGACUCAGCCUCCUGAGCAGCUGGGAUUACAGGUGCCUGCCACCACGCCCAGCUAAUUUCGUAUUUUUAGUAGAGACAGGGUUUCUCCAUGUCGGUCAGGCUGGUCUCGGACUCCUGACCUCAGGUGAUCCACCCACCUCGGCCUCCCAAAGUGCUGGGAUUACAGGUGUGAGCCACCGCGCCCAGCCUGGCCUGGCCCAUUUCUAAUUGACUUCCUCUCUUCAACUUCAGCCUCCCUCCAGUCCUUUCUCCACACUGUAUCUAGGGGGAUGGUUUCAAGAUGCACAUUCCACCAAUGGCUCCUCCUUGAAGUUGAUCUUCUGCUUAAAAGCUUUCAAUAGGCACCCUUGCCCUCAAGAUGAAGACCAAAAUCCAGACCCCAAAGGCCCUGGCCAGGCCUCUCUGUCCACUUUAAUCUUUGACCAUUUCCCCCUGACUGUCUGAGCUCCAGCCUCAGAGCCUUUCCACAUAUUGUUCCAUUUGCUUGACUCUCUCUUCCUCUUCUCUUCCUCAUUAUUGCCACUUUGCCUAAUUAACUUCUUUAGACCCUUAAACAUCACUUCAUCAGGGAAGCCCUCCCCUAGUCUUACACAAGGCCAGGCCCCCCUAUUGUAGAGUCUCAUAACACAAUCUUUGUCUUUUACACCCUUUAUCUCAGUAGGCAGUUCUUUAUUUUUUAUUUUUUGAGAUAAGAGUUUCACUCUUUUUGCCCAGGCUGGGGUGCAAUGGCGUGACCUCGGCUCACUGCAACCUCUGCCUCCUGGAUUCAAGUGAUUCUCCUGCCUCAGCCUCCCAAGUAGUUGGGAUUACAGGCGCCUACCACCACGCCCAGCUAAUUUUGUGUUUUUAGUAGAGACGGGCCUUCACCAUGUUAGCCAGGCUGGUCUCGAACUCCUGACCUCAGGUGAUUUGCCUGCCUUGGCCUCCCAAAGUGCUAGGAUUACAGGCGUGAGCCACCACUCCUGGUCUCAGUUUGUAAUUCUUUAAAUUUUAGUCAUUGGUUUAACUCUUGCCCCUUAGUCUGUAAGCUGCAGGAGUGCAGAUACCUUUGAGUUCUUGGUGCCUAGCACAGGUCUGGUCCAGAGCAGACCUGCAAUCAAUAUUGUGGAAUAAAUGAGUCCAGCUGUGGCCAGCCUUAAACGCCUGCUAAGCAAUUUAGGCCAUAUCCUGUUGGCUGUGGAAAACUGUUGGAGAGAAUCAGGGAUUUAGGGCUUUGGGAAGAUUAACAGAUUGGAGGGGAGGAACAUGUGGAGGGCUUGUGGAAAGGAUAAAAAUUAGGCAGAAACUUCAGAACUUACGAGGAAACUACUGUUAGCCCCAUCUUCCAGACUGAGAAAACUAAGGCUCAAAGAGGUUAAGUAACUUACUCGAAAUCACAUACCUGGUGAGUAGCUGAGCCAGAAAUCCAGCCCAGGCCUACCAGAUCCCAGAGCCUGAGCUCUUUAUCAUGUGCUAAACUGCCUCUGUGACCCACUACUGCUUGUCAACAGUGGCCCACAAGUGCUUCAGGGGCAUGUGUGGGGCCUGGUGUUGUGGAUCUUCCACACGUAGAAGAGACUGGACGCCACGGGCAAUCAGUUGGUGUUUUCUGAAUGGACGGAUGGGACCAUGUAACAGGAAUGUCAAAGGCAGGAGAAGCAGCAAAGCUUUACACCCAGCUCAUUCUCCUGGAAGCCGCCAUGAAGCAGUCUUUUCCCUCCAGUCCACGAACUACCUGAGGGCAGGGACUGCAUUUGCAGUCAGAAAUGUCAGAGUCAGAGAUGUAGGGUCUGAAAACCUAGUUCAAGUCCUCACUCGAGCACUUACAAGGAAGGCAUGUGACCUCUCCGAGUCUGUCUCUCUGAUGGUAAUAGGAGGAAUUGGAGGAAUUCCAGGAUAACCUGGGUGAGGGCCCUCUGCAGCCUAAGUUCUGAGACACAGUGUCCUCAGUUUACUUACCUGACCAGCGGGCUUAAUAAUUUCCAACCUGUGACGUGGCUUUUUUGUGGCUCUUUUUUUUUUUUUAGACAAUGUCUUGCUCUGUCGCCCAGGCUGGAGUACAGUGGUGUGAUCUCGGCUCACUGCAAUCUCUGCCUCCCAGAUUCAAGCCAUUCUCCUGUCUCAGCCUCCCGAGUAGCUGGGACUACAGGCGCAUACCACCAUACCUGGUUAAUUUUUAUAUUUUUAGUAGAGACGGGAUUUCGCCAUAUUGGUCAGGCUGGUCUUGAACUCCUGACCUCAGGUGAUCCGCCCGCCUCGGCCUCCCAAAGUGCUGGGAUUACAGCCGUGAGCCACUGCUUCCAGCUGACAUGGCUCUUUCUAAUGCCAUCUGCUGUUAUUACUAUCAUCAUUGUCAUUAUUAGUCCUUGACUGCAGACAGAUGGCUUUAAGGAAGUCAAAUAUAGAGUUUACACCUGGAGAGGGAGGCACAGGGGUGAGAGAGGACAAGGUGUGAUCUACUUUUAAGGGAGCACACCCGCGCUUCCCCUACUUGCCCCCAGAAGACCAAAGCCAUGAGCAGGAACCUCUUUAGGAGGACAAGUUGAGCCACAGGCCAGCCUGGGUCACAUCUUGUCCCCACCCUGCCCUGAAGAGAAGCUCUGCAGGAGACCAGGCAGCCAGGGCAAAGGGCCUAAAAAUGCCAAGGCCUGAUUUGCAUAGGCAAAGAGCAGCCUCCUCAUCUCUCCUCCAGCCUUCCAGAGACUUCCUGCAUUUGUAGCUCUUGAGAUCUGUGGCCUGAAAGGCGCUGGAAGCAGAGCCUGUGAGUGUGGUCCCCGUCACCAGAGCCCCAACCCACCGCCGCCAUGGUAGGAAAAGGUGCCAAAGGGAUGCUGAAUGGUGCUGUGCCCAGCGAGGCCACCAAGAGGGACCAGAACCUCAAACGGGGCAACUGGGGCAACCAGAUCGAGUUUGUACUGACGAGCGUGGGCUAUGCCGUGGGCCUGGGCAAUGUCUGGCGCUUCCCAUACCUCUGCUAUCGCAACGGGGGAGGCGCCUUCAUGUUCCCCUACUUCAUCAUGCUCAUCUUCUGCGGGAUCCCCCUCUUCUUCAUGGAGCUCUCCUUCGGCCAGUUUGCAAGCCAGGGGUGCCUGGGGGUCUGGAGGAUCAGCCCCAUGUUCAAAGGAGUGGGCUAUGGUAUGAUGGUGGUGUCCACCUACAUCGGCAUCUACUACAAUGUGGUCAUCUGCAUCGCCUUCUACUACUUCUUCUCGUCCAUGACGCACGUGCUGCCCUGGGCCUACUGCAAUAACCCCUGGAACACGCAUGACUGCGCCGGUGUACUGGACGCCUCCAACCUCACCAAUGGCUCUCGGCCAGCCGCCUUGCCCAGCAACCUCUCCCACCUGCUCAACCACAGCCUCCAGAGGACCAGCCCCAGCGAGGAGUACUGGAGGCUGUACGUGCUGAAGCUGUCAGAUGACAUUGGGAACUUUGGGGAGGUGCGGCUGCCCCUCCUUGGCUGCCUCGGUGUCUCCUGGUUGGUCGUCUUCCUCUGCCUCAUCCGAGGGGUCAAGUCUUCAGGGAAAGUGGUGUACUUCACGGCCACGUUCCCCUACGUGGUGCUGACCAUUCUGUUUGUCCGCGGAGUGACCCUGGAGGGAGCCUUUGACGGCAUCAUGUACUACCUAACCCCGCAGUGGGACAAGAUCCUGGAGGCCAAGGUGUGGGGUGAUGCUGCCUCCCAGAUCUUCUACUCACUGGGCUGCGCGUGGGGAGGCCUCAUCACCAUGGCUUCCUACAACAAGUUCCACAAUAACUGUUACCGGGACAGUGUCAUCAUCAGCAUCACCAACUGUGCCACCAGCGUCUAUGCUGGCUUCGUCAUCUUCUCCAUCCUCGGCUUCAUGGCCAAUCACCUGGGCGUGGAUGUGUCCCGUGUGGCAGACCACGGCCCUGGCCUGGCCUUCGUGGCUUACCCCGAGGCCCUCACACUACUUCCCAUCUCCCCGCUGUGGUCUCUGCUCUUCUUCUUCAUGCUUAUCCUGCUGGGGCUGGGCACUCAGUUCUGCCUCCUGGAGACGCUGGUCACAGCCAUUGUGGAUGAGGUGGGGAAUGAGUGGAUCCUGCAGAAAAAGACCUAUGUGACCUUGGGCGUGGCUGUGGCUGGCUUCCUGCUGGGCAUCCCCCUCACCAGCCAGGCAGGCAUCUAUUGGCUGCUGCUGAUGGACAACUAUGCGGCCAGCUUCUCCUUGGUGGUCAUCUCCUGCAUCAUGUGUGUGGCCAUCAUGUACAUCUACGGGCACCGGAACUACUUCCAGGACAUCCAGAUGAUGCUGGGAUUCCCACCACCCCUCUUCUUUCAGAUCUGCUGGCGCUUCGUCUCUCCCGCCAUCAUCUUCUUUAUUCUAGUUUUCACUGUGAUCCAGUACCAGCCGAUCACCUACAACCACUACCAGUACCCAGGCUGGGCCGUGGCCAUUGGCUUCCUCAUGGCUCUGUCCUCCGUCCUCUGCAUCCCCCUCUACGCCAUGUUCCGGCUCUGCCGCACAGACGGGGACACCCUCCUCCAGCGUUUGAAAAAUGCCACAAAGCCAAGCAGAGACUGGGGCCCUGCCCUCCUGGAGCACCGGACAGGGCGCUACGCCCCCACCAUAGCCCCCUCUCCUGAGGACGGCUUCGAGGUCCAGCCACUGCACCCGGACAAGGCGCAGAUCCCCAUUGUGGGCAGUAAUGGCUCCAGCCGCCUCCAGGACUCCCGGAUAUGAGCACAGCUGCCAGGGGAGUGGCCCCACCCCCACCCCGUGCUCCCACCGCAGAGACUGGUGAGGCAGAGGCCAGGUGUCUCUGCCUGCCCCCUGCCACGCCCUGGCCAGGACGGCUGCUGUCACCUUGGUCACCACUGCUAGUGCAGUCAUUCAUGCUCAUGUCCCCAGUGUUUACAUGUCCUUUGGAUGCCAAGAUAGCAGCUGGGGGGAGGGGUGGGAGUGGAGGGUUGCUGGGAGGUCCAAAGCACUUUGGAGGGGUCUCGGGCCAGGUCCCCAGCAGCCUGGAUGGCUUUACGUGGCCUCCGAUACCCUUAUACCCUGCCCUGAGCUGAGGUUCUGGGUGGGCCUCCAGCCCCAUGACUAGUGCUCCUGCCCUCAGAGCCGACCCCAGCCUCUGCCAGGCACAUUUGGCUAUUCCUCCCUAGGGGCAGGAUGAAGGGCUGGGGGACUGCCCAGUGUUACUUGUCAGGCUGUGCUGCCCAGCCCUGUUUAUCUGUGUAAUUAUUUUUGUAAACAUUGUAUUCUCUGUGGUCGCCACCUCCUCGCCCCCAGCCUCGGGUUCAGUCUGUCUUCCAGGCCUGCUUGCACCUCACUGGGCUGCUCCGGGGUCUCUGCCCCUCAUUCCAGGCCUGGCUGUCAGGCCCAGCCAGCAGGGGCCCGUGACCCAGCAGCCUGCCCAAAGCAUUUGUUUCUGGGGGAUGGGGUGGGGGCUGCUCCACAGGAGGUUUGAGCCCAGCACCCUGGGGAAGGGGACCCUGCACGACACCCCCUUGCCCUCCCUCCAUGAGGCUAAAGGCCCAGUCUUCCCAAAUGUGCUGCCCUCGUUCAUGUGCCAAAUGGCCCCAGCCCACAUGCCCCUCCCCUCUCUGGAGUGGGAGCCCCUUCUGAAGUGUCUGAAUCCCUGAAGUGUUCAUUUGUCCGUCCUCUGUGCAGUGACAGCCCCGGCCAAGCCACCUCUAAUCCUCUGUAGCAAUAACGGUGCGCCGCCCAUCCCUGCCCAUUGUGCACCACUAGGAUUUUAAAGUCCAUAGAUUUUAAUGAAAUUUCUAUUCCUGUCUCUGA